AGUGCUCAGCGGCAGCCACUAUGGAGGCCGCCAGGACCGCUGUACUCCGGGUGAAGCGGAAGCGCAGUGCGGAGCCGGCGGAGGCUCUUGUGCUCGCUUGUAAACGCCUCCGGAGCGACGCGGUCGAGUCAGCGGCACAGAAGACGUCGGAGGGUUUGGAGAGAGCGGCGGAGAAUAAUGUCUUCCACUUGGUGGCCACUGUGUGCUCCCAGGAGGAACCAGUCCAGCCUCUCCUGCGGGAAGUUCUGCGCCCGUCACGGGACAGCCAGCAGCGUGUCCGCCGUAAUCUCCGCGCCUCGGCUCGGGAGGUCCGGCAGGAGGGCCGCUACCGGGUGCUUUCCAGCCGCCGAUCCUUGGGGACCACCUCGAGCGGCCAGGAGUCCGAGUACACGCCGGGGAACCCAGAAGCCGCCGGGAACUCGGGCUUUCAGUUGUUAGACCUUGUCCACGAGGAGGGAGAACCUGAAGCCGCCUCUGCAGGCUCCUGCAAAACAUCUGACCCAGAUGUGAUCCUCUGCAAUUCUGUAGAGUUGAUCCGUGAGCGAUUGACUGUGUCUGAGGAUGGACCAGGAGUCAGGCGCCAGGAAGAACAAAAACACGAUGACUAUGUGUAUGACAUUUACUACUUGGAGACGGCCACUCCAGGCUGGAUUGAGAACAUCCUCUCCGUGCAGCCCUACAGCCAAGAAUGGGAGCUGGUGAAUGAUGAUCAAGAACCAGAGGACAUUUACGACGAUGAAGAUGACGAGAACAGUGAGAAUAACUGGCGCAAUGAGUACCCAGAGGAGGAGAGCAGUGAUGGAGAUGAGGAUUCCAGAGGCUCUGCUGACUACAACAGCCUGAGUGAGGAGGAAAGAGGCAGCAGCAGACAGCGGAUGUGGAGCAAGUACCCUCUGGAUGUGCAGAAGGAGUUCGGCUAUGACAGCCCCCACGACCUGGAUUCAGACUGAUGGUCUUGUGAUGUCCAUGAGGUUCUGCCACAUGCCCUUGAGGGCUCUGAGUCCAGAGUUAACUGCCCUGCUGACAUCCUGUUAGGUUUCCUAGCUUAACAUGUGGAAGGAAAAGCAUAUCAAGCAUAUCGGGCGGCACCAUCCCACCACAGUGAAAACUUAUGUUAGGGGAGUGAGUCUUUUCCACUUACAGUAGGACCCCUUUGCCUCAAUCAAAAGUGACCCUACAGUUUGAAAGAAAAAAAAACGUUGAAAAAAGGAAGGUUUCUUUAGCUUUAGCUUCUUGGCCCAGGAAUUUUUCCUGGCAUUCAGGUUCUGUGCUGAAACCACAAGGGAGGGGGAGGUUCCCAUUUCAUUAGCAGUAAGCUUCUGCUGUGCCAUACCACCAGGCUGCCUGCCUCUAGGAAAACCCUGUUCCUUUUGAUAGAAUCUAAAAGGGGUACCAGUGGGUCCCUUGUAGCAAUACAGACUGGAUAGUAAUGGCCAUUAGGGCAGAAAGUAGUCUGAGCAGUGGGAGAUUUUAGUUAACAGCUAUUUCUGCUUCCAAACUCUGAUAACGGUUGUGAAAUUACUGACUGACUUCCUUUGGCAGUGGGGCCAAGAAACAAUAUAUAUGAAUGUGAUACAUGUGUUUAGUAAAAUCUAGCUUUGAACAUGGAAGAAAGUAAUUCUUUGAAAACCUUUUAAAUCUGAAUAUCUAAAACAGGGAGCGGUAGUGAAAUAGAAGGUUCAGCAUUGAUUAUAAAUACCAAGGACUUAAGGCAAGGGAGGAAAAACAAAGUACCUUCUGAACUUAGCUUUCCACUGAGUAAUGUUUACUCUUCACAGCACCCACCACAAAAACAAACUACUAUCAACAGGAUCAAUUUUAUUAACAACUUGUAUCUCUUCUAAGCAGACUCUGUCCGUAUGCCUUUCCAAACCAUAGCUGCCUUAACUGACUGCCUUGGUGUUUAUUCUAGCGUAACAUUGUCCAGUAGAACUAUCUGCAGUGAUGAUAUGUUCUGUGUCUGCACUGUGUAGUAGUAGACACGGGUGGCUGCUGAGCACUUGAAAUGUGAUUAGCGCAACUGAGAAACUGAGCUUUUAAUUUUAUUUCAUUUUAAUGUAAUUAGCUACACGUGGCUAGUAGCUGUUGCAGCGGACACCACAGGUCUAAGGAAACAACACAGAACAUUCAGCUAGGGGUGUACCCUCAUAGCCUGUGAGUGUCUCUUACUCACUGUCAUGGGGGAAGGUGAGUUACACAGGGAGGUACCUUCUUGCCGCCUCUUUUAGGAUUUCCUAAGUAUCUCUCCUUCAUCCUACCUGCCAUCAUUCUUUGACUUUAUGUCCAUUUUCUAAACCUUUGCCUACACUUGCUCUUAUCUACAUGGAGUUGUUCAACCUGCCGAAGUGAUUAAAUUCUGUGUACACAGGCCGUAUAUAUUGCAGCUAAUUAAAACAACAAACAUCCUAGGCAUGCACAAAGGUAUAAUUCACCGUUAUAACAGGCAGCAACUUGUAUGUCUAAUAUUAGACAUCUUGCUUUCUGUCUGUAGGCAUAGAAACAAAGGAUUGAAAGCCAUUCUCAUACAGCAACCGGGUGAAAAAAACAAAACACUGUGCUGUUACAAUGUGCUCCCUGCUAUUUAUACUCAUUAAGUUUCCCCAAUAUUAAAGGGCUGACAACUUAAUAAACUGUACUCACUGCAAAAGGGAUAAUAAGCACACCAGGAAAAGGAUUUAAGGAGACAGACAACAAAGAGCUGGCAGAAAUUAAUUCCACCAUGAAGCUUGAGUGCUGUAGGGAUCCUCUGGCUUCGCUCCCAAAGAGAGGAUCCUGGGAGAAGUCUGUAUCCAGCACAGAGGGGAAAAAUGCUGUCACCAUCCAAAAAUGAAAGGAGGAUGACAUGGCUCACUAAGCAAGUACUAGGGCACCUGGCAUGUGAGGUCCUUGCUUUCCCUAGAAGCCACUGGUGGGGGGCAGCAAAUUCCUGGGAUUAGCUGGUUAUCUGGUGGAGAAAGCUAAAGCUGGGGUCAGGGAUCUUUAAAAGGCAAGCACAUUUUGCUUAAAGGAUUAGCUCCAGAGGAGCCCUGGGAUGGGUGCCAGCUUAGCUCAGACAGAAGUCAUGUUCUUAGCGUUCAGGCAAGUCAGCCUUUGCAUAAGACACCCUGUCGUCGGGCAGGAAUUUGCCGUUACAAAUCCCAAACCCAUGACAGUAGGAAUGUCACCCCAUGCUUCACAUAUGCAUUAUGCUCUGAACCCAGGGCAACUAUGACCAUGCUUCCUUCAAUCUUUAUUGAGCAAAUAUAUGGCCAAGGUUAUUCCCUUAUCUGUGACUGGGUGGAGAAGAAUGGUCAGGAAGGGAGACUGCCUCACUGUUGACCAAUUCCAAAACCUAAGGAUAAGCCCAUGGGGUAUGUCAAGCUAGCAGGUUCUUCUCGGCCCAGGAUGACAGUGUCUGGGGGCAUCACAAAACAGUUGUACAAUCCAAUGCAGCCGUCCUGCUCAUACAGUAAGAUCCAUUAGGCCAGAGCAGGCCUAACUUGGGUGGAGAGCCCAGCCUGAGCACCAGAAUUAGUUGCUUCCACUUGUGCAGCCUGCUGAAGAGCCGGACUCAGGUUGAAGCAGCUUUCCUCCCAGUCUUCACUGAUCUCCACAGGGAGAAAACAGAAGUCCCCACAAGUACCAAGCUCUUCCUGAGACUGCAGCCACCACACCUCGGGGAAGGGGAGGCUGGCAGGAGAGGAGUACACUGUCCCGGUGACCCACACCAAGGUGGCUCCAAGUGUAAACAAAGCCUGGUGCCAGGGACAGAAGAGGAUGCAGCCUGAUGUGAGGUUUUCAGAAAAGUGAAAUGACCUAGCACCAGGUUGGGAUUGCUUGGGUCUGCACAGCAGUCCCUCACACUGCCCUUACAGAGAGGAACAGGUUAUUUGAUGACUUGGGCCCAUGAGAUGUUCUCCAAGCCAUUGACAGCUGAGAGAAUUCAGGUGAUCCACCUGAAUAUCAGAAGUUUCAGCCCUCUUAGAGUUCGUAACAGAAACCCAGAGAUUUACUGUCAGCUAGAACAAAGAUGUAAGGUCUCAAGUAAAAUAAAGGAUUGUCCUUCAAAACAGCAAUAUUAACAGACUUCUGACUCAGGAAUUUGUUCAUCUGUCCUUGCUGGACCUGAGCCAAGUGCUUGUAACGUGAUCUAUGAUCUAUCUGUAUGCUAAAGUGUAACAGGUACGUGAGUAAAAAAAUCUUUAAGGUUCA